CUCCGGCGCCUGGCUCCCUGCAGGCGAGGAGCGGAAGCCGCUAUCUGGAGGCGGACUCCGGCGCCACAGAGCCGGGGCAGCCGCGGCAACGGCGAGGCGCGAGGCAGGGGCGCCCGGCAGACCCCGCGACCCCGAGCCAGCGGGCGCCCCGAGCGGGCAGCCUCGCCGGGGGAGGCGGAGGCGGCCACGGCGGCCGCGCUCGGGCGCCCCUCGCGCAGCGCUCCAUGCCCGUGUGGUGCUGCCGCUGCUCCCUGGCCGGUCAUUUCAGAAACUAUAGUGACACUGAAACUGAAGGAGAGAUUUUUAAUUCCUUAGUGCAAUACUUUGGUGACAACUUGGGGCGAAAAGUUAAAGCGAUGCCAUUAGUUGAAGAAACUUCUUUACUGGAAGAUUCGUCAGUGACUUUUCCUGUGGUAAUAAUAGGAAAUGGACCCUCAGGAAUAUGCCUUUCUUAUAUGUUAUCAGGCUACAGACCGUAUUUAUCAUCAGAAGCAAUACACCCAAAUACAAUCUUAAAUAGUAAAUUAGAAGAAGCAAGACAUCUUUCCAUUGUUGAUCAGGACUUAGAAUACUUGUCUGAGGGCCUUGAGGGCCGAUCAUCCAAUCCAGUUGCAGUACUUUUCGAUACACUUCUUCAUCCAGAUGCUGACUUUGGGUAUGAUUAUCCAUCCGUUUUGCAUUGGAAAUUAGAGCAACAUCAUUAUAUCCCUCACGUAGUUCUUGGUAAAGGUCCACCUGGUGGGGCUUGGCAUAAUAUGGAAGGCUCCAUGUUGACAAUCAGCUUUGGAAGUUGGAUGGAACUACCUGGACUUAAAUUUAAGGACUGGGUAUCAAGUAAACGAAGGAGCCUAAAAGGGGAUCGAGUUAUGCCAGAGGAAAUAGCUCGCUACUAUAAACAUUAUGUAAAAGUCAUGGGUCUUCAGAAGAAUUUCAGAGAGAAUACUUACAUAACUUCCGUAUCAAGACUCUACAGAGAUCAAGAUGAUGAUGAUAUUCAAGACAGAGAUAUUUCAACAAAGCAUUUACAGAUAGAGAAGUCAAACUUUAUCAAGAGAAACUGGGAAAUUAGGGGUUAUCAGCGAAUAGCUGAUGGUUCUCAUGUUCCCUUCUGCCUCUUUGCUGAGAAUGUAGCGCUGGCAACUGGAACGCUGGAUUCUCCUGCCCAUCUGGAAAUUGAAGGGGAAGAUUUUCCUUUUGUGUUUCAUUCAAUGCCUGAAUUUGGAGCUGCUAUAAACAAAGGAAAGUUGCGUGGCAAAGUGGAUCCAGUGUUAAUUGUAGGUUCUGGGCUUACUGCCGCUGACGCAGUACUGUGUGCUUACAACAGUAAUAUCCCUGUGAUUCAUGUGUUUCGCAGACGAGUAACUGAUCCAAGCUUAAUUUUCAAACAGCUUCCCAAAAAGCUGUAUCCUGAAUAUCAUAAAGUCUAUCAUAUGAUGUGUACUCAGUCAUAUUCUGUAGACUCAAAUCUUUUAUCUGAUUAUACCAGCUUUCCCGAGCACCGUGUGCUUUCCUUUAAGUCGGACAUGAAAUGUGUUCUCCAAAGCGUUUCUGGAUUGAAGAAAAUAUUUAAGCUGUCUGCAGCAGUAGUAUUGAUAGGUUCUCAUCCUAAUCUGUCUUUUCUGAAGGAUCAAGGGUGUUACCUAGGCCAUAAGUCAAGCCAGCCAAUCACAUGUAAGGGUAAUCCUGUGGAAAUAGAUACAUAUACCUAUGAGUGUAUUAAAGAAGCCAACCUUUUUGCAUUGGGUCCUUUGGUUGGAGACAAUUUUGUUCGAUUUUUAAAGGGAGGGGCGCUGGGUGUUACACGCUGUUUAGCUACAAGACAGAAGAAAAAGCAUUUGUUUGUUGAAAGAGGAGGAGGAGAUGGGAUAGCUUAAAGCAAGUUUACAAGUAAUUAAAAUGGACAGUUUGCCAUUAAAGAUUUUUAAUAGUGGUUUUGCAGUGUACUGGCUUGAAUUUUCUGGACUUGAGUUAACUGAAGGAGAGCCUCAAACUAUAGUAACUUCAUUUUUAAAAGUUACUAGAAUUUGGUAUCCUGAUUUAUAUUGCAGUGUUUCAAAGGUGUCACUGUCAGACAAAUAGAAACACUGCCAACUUGGUGUAACUUAAGCUUUCAUUUAACUAAAACAUUCUUUUCUUGCAAAACUUAUUUUUCAUGAUCAUUUUUGGUUAUUUAUUAUACUUGAUUCCAAAAUAGUACAGCCUUGAAUCUAUAAAACUGUGCAGUCAUUAUGCCAGAAAUUAUCUUAAAUAUAUAAUGGGUCACCUUGCUGUUCAAAGGGUGGUGCAAGGUCCUGCAGCAUCUUACAUCUGUAGCUUGUUAGAAAUGUAAACUCUCAGGCCCCACAACUUACUUCCUGCAUUUUAACAAGAUCCCCAAGGGAUAUGUAUGCUCAUAAAAAUUUGAGACACUGGUUUAAAUGAAAAUGGAUAUAAGGUAUGUAUAACUGGGGGUGGGGUGAGGGUAGGAGGCAUUUACAACUCAGAUUUUAUUUAUUUUGAAAUUAUCAAUUGUAUAAAUCUAAUUUAUUACCAAAUAGGGUCUUUUAAAAAAUAUUUUUAUCGUUGAAACCUUGACAGGUACUUCAUAUUCUUCUAAUAAUUUAAACAGUCCAAUAAUGUGGUAUACACUUUGACAUCCAAGAACUCACCAAGAUGUUUUUCAGAGAUUUAUUCUCGAUUUAACUAUCAUAGCAUUUAAUGAAUCUGAUUUGUAGUUCAAUAAAUUGUGGGUUGAACUACUUAUCCCUGUGUGAACAUUGAAUUACUUUCUGUCACUGAAACUGAGGUAUUUGGGUGUGGUAAGUACUUCGAAAAUUGUAAUACUGUUUGGGCAUUGUCUAAAUUAUUAAAGGUUAAAAUAGAAAAUAAAGUCAGAAUUUUUCUUUUCCAUUCCAAAGGUGUACUUAGAGAUCUCUAUUAGUAUUCAUUCGAGAUGACAUAGCAGCUCAUAUCAUGGUUGUUUAUUGGAUUUAUCUGUUCUAAUUAUAUAAGUGUGUUUACUGUCUGUGUUUUCACACAAACUGCUAGAAUUUUUAAUGUUAAGACGAAAACAUCUGAAGUUCUCCAUGGCAAAUUGAAUUUUUCAGUCAUUUUCUUUUCUUUUUUUGGUACAAUUACUUCAUCUGGAAUGUCUUCAUUGAACUCGUUAUUCUAUUUUUCUUAGAAUUAAAAGUGGAUUAAUGUGGGUUUUUCUGUUCAUUUUAUUGCAGUAUUAAAUGCUUAAGCUUAUUAGGACCAUAAUUCACUUUAAAUAUAAUUGUAUAGAAUAUAUUUGCGUCGAUCAAAUAAUUGCUUCAGAUGAAUUCUUAGACUCUUGAUAAUAUCACACCUAAUUUAACUUGAUUUUACAAGCUGUACAAUCCAGUUUUAGUUUUCUAUUGUGAUAAUAACUUUUUUCAAACCAGUUUCACAUCUUAAUGAAAUAACAUUCUCUGACUGCACUUGCUUCAGUACUCUCUUGCCUGCCUGUUUUUGACCUCUGCAUGAGUUGGAUUAGAUGUUUUUCUUACUGUCACUUCUAAAUAGAAAAUGACAGUGUUAUAAAAAAGGGAAGGAUAAAACCUUUGACAUCCCCUUGUGUCUCAAAAGUCCACAGUUAUUCAAACAAUGGCUUUUUUUGUGAUGAGAGUAUUUGUUAAAAAAAAAAAAAGACUUCAAGAAAAAUAAAAGUUCAGUGGAGCUGCAAAUAAAUCUGGUGAAUAAUUUCAUCUUUGGUAAUCUCCCAUUUCCUGAGUUCUUCCUCAAUCCAAGCUGUCCUGUGUAGUAUAUAACAUUUGGGCAUUUUCUCUGAUAUACUAUACUCUCAUGUUCUAUAAAUUUCUGUCCCGUAAUUCUAACACUUUACAUUUUUUCUUUGCUAUCAGCUAUAGCUAUUCAUGGAAGGGAAGAAUCACUAAAUACUUGUCUAGUUAUAGCAUGAUGUGAGCAUCUCCUCCUUAUCCCUCGAUGCCUGGCUUGGUGUCUGGCAAACAGUCCAUAAUUAGCAGAUGUUGAAAGACCGUUUACAAAGCAGAAUUUGGGGAUUUAAAGUGCAAUGAUACAACAAAAAGAUUUAAUUACAGCUUCCAGUGUUUUGACUAUGUGAACCAUAUCCAACUACUUUUUUGAAAAUCUAGUUCUAUGUAAUAUAUUUCUGUGGCAUCAAAUUUUAGUUGAUUGUAUUAGUCAAUAGGAAGUGGUGGAAAAUUUCUAAAUAAAUUCAACUAUUAAAUAAAUGCAAGUUCCACUAAA